ACUCUGGGGCUGGCGCAAGCCCUCAGCGACGCCGGGCGCGUGCGUUCCGCUGCCUCCAGCCCCUGGGCACCGCUGCCGUGCGCUCGCUGGCGGGGAGAGGCCUGCAGAAGUCAGGCCAGGUGUCUCUCUUUCCCUUGGGCCCGCGGCCCAACCGCAUGGCACCAGGCAGCCCCCAGCGGUAUUGCGACCUCUGCGUCAGUCGCGCUCAGUCCCUAGAUACAGGUGUGCCGGAGAAGCCCAGGGAAGGGAUGCGUGACCAUCACUACACCCUGCCCCACGACGCGGUGGGACGCGCACCCUGACCCUCCCCAGAGCCGCGCCCAGGACCUUGCCUGGGCGGAAAAUGGCAGCCGUUGCCGGGAAGGAGCGGCGAGCGAGAGGCAGGCCCCGGCCAGAGACACUGGGAGCCAUCCCUAGGAGGGAGGGAGGCGAGGCGGGCUUGAGCCGAGCCUUCAAGCCACUGGCGCAGGCGCCAUUGUCCUGUGAGACUUCGCUGAGAAAACUCAAAUUCAAAGGUAAAAAGCAUGGCUCUGUGAGCGCUGAUGAGGCUGCCCGCACGGCUCCCUUCCACCUCGACCUCUGGUUCUACUUCACACUGCAGAACUGGGUUCUGGACUUUGGGCGUCCCAUUGCCAUGCUGGUAUUCCCUCUCGAGUGGUUUCCACUCAACAAGCCCAGUGUUGGGGACUACUUCCACAUGGCCUACAACGUCAUCACGCCCUUUCUCUUGCUCAAGCUCAUCGAGCGGUCCCCCCGCACCCUGCCACGCUCCAUCACGUACGUGAGCAUCAUCAUCUUCAUCAUGGGUGCCAGCAUCCACCUGGUGGGUGACUCUGUCAACCACCGCCUGCUCUUCAGUGGCUACCAGCACCACCUGUCUGUCCGUGAGAACCCCAUCAUCAAGAAUCUCAAGCCGGAGACGCUGAUCGACUCCUUUGAGCUGCUCUACUAUUAUGAUGAGUACCUGGGUCACUGCAUGUGGUACAUCCCCUUCUUCCUCAUCCUCUUCAUGUACUUCAGCGGCUGCUUUACUGCCUCUAAAGCUGAGAGCUUGAUUCCAGGGCCUGCCCUGCUCCUGGUGGCACCCAGUGGCCUGUACUACUGGUACCUGGUCACCGAGGGCCAGAUCUUCAUCCUCUUCAUCUUCACCUUCUUCGCCAUGCUGGCCCUCGUCCUGCACCAGAAGCGCAAGCGCCUCUUCCUGGACAGCAACGGCCUCUUCCUCUUCUCCUCCUUCGCACUGACCCUCUUGCUUGUGGCGCUCUGGGUCGCCUGGCUGUGGAAUGACCCUGUUCUCAGGAAGAAGUACCCGGGUGUCAUCUACGUCCCUGAGCCCUGGGCUUUCUACACCCUUCACGUCAGCAGUCGGCACUGAGUCCCUGGCACCAGGCUCUGGCGCUCUGCUGGGUGGGAGGGUGGGCCAUGGAGGGCAUCUGAAUACAGGAGUAGGGGGGGUGUGGGUGUGUAACCAGAGACCGAGAGCAUGAGUGGGGUGUGCCUCGUGUGCGUGGAUUCGUGUGUGUGUGUGUGUGUGUCUUGUAUAUGUGUGCGCAGAGUGCAUCAUUUUCAGACUCUACUAUUUCCGUCAAGUUUCUGUUUGAUUUGGAUCAUCUCAGGAUCGGAUUCUGUUUUAGAGUGUUUCUGGGCCAGGAUCCGGGCCCCUGCCCUCCUCUGCACCUGACCACACUCCCUACUCAGGGCUAGUCUGUUCUUCCCGGACAUCUUCUGGUAGCCGUGCAGGAGAGGGCUGGGUGGGGCAGAGGCCAGGAGGGGACCUGGUGUGUCACCUGCCCACCACCUGGCUCAUCCCUCAGGCCCACCCUGACCCUACAUUACAUAGGUUACGUCAGCCUACUGUGGCUGUUGAGCAAAGCAUUUCUCCUUUCUGGGCCUCAUUUGCACUAGAUGGGCCUGUGGUCCCAAAGUAGGUCAGUAGGUUGGGGUUGCUGACACCCCUUGGGUGCAGCUUUGGGACAGAUGAGUGGCUCUGUCCUGUCACUGCCCUCUCCCUGCCUGGGGGCUAUGUGCACUCCAGACCCCUGCCCAGGCUCAGGCCCAUGAGGUAUGGAGACACCCUGGCCCCCAGGAGCUGGAGGCACCGCCCACUCCCCUGGCAUUCCAGCUUUGCAGGUGACCCUCCUCUACCCAAAGCUCUGUCCCCCUGCUCCCACUCCAGAAGAACUGCGGCACGCGCUUCGGGCAGCCUAGCCACAGGCUUUGAGCGCCUGCAUUCCUGGGGGCUGGAGGGUGGGGUGCCAAAGGCCCUGAGCAAAAGCCAGAGCUCCUCUCAUCAAAGCCUUUACAAGGUGCUGGGCCCAGAGGCUUUGCCUUGACAGAGUGGCCCAGGGUUUCAAGGGAGGAGGAACCUCCCCCUACCUAGGACCCUUCCUGUGGGGGGUCUACAGAGUCAGGGACAGAAGGGAAGGGACCCACAGGAAGUCACAGUGGUGCCCAGGGAUGUGUCAGCCCCCAGCCACGGGGACGCGGGAUUCAAGAAUGAAGUAAAUACAGUCACAGCCCCAA